AACUAUGUUGCUGCUGGAGAUCAAUGAAGCCGAGUGAAUGGGGGCUGAAUGUGCGAGUCCAUAGCUGAAGAGGAGCGCCAGAUGGUGGAGGAAUACACUUAUUUAUGAAACUGUCUUGAGUUCUUCUUGAAUUGCCAGUUUUCAGCCUCCUCAUGCCUCCGUCUCCUUUAGACGACAGGGUAGUAGUGGCACUAUCUAGGCCCGUCCGACCUCAGGAUCUCAACCUUUGUUUAGACUCUAGUUACCUUGGCUCUGCCAACCCAGGCAGUAACAGCCACCCUCCUGUCAUCGCCACCACCGUUGUGUCCCUCAAGGCUGCGAAUCUGACGUAUAUGCCCUCAUCCAGCGGCUCUGCCCGCUCGCUGAAUUGUGGAUGCAGCAGUGCCAGCUGCUGCACUGUGGCAACCUACGACAAGGACAAUCAGGCCCAAACCCAAGCCAUUGCCGCUGGCACCACCACCACUGCCAUCGGAACCUCUACCACCUGCCCUGCUAACCAGAUGGUCAACAAUAAUGAGAAUACAGGCUCUCUAAGUCCAUCAAGUGGGGUGGGCAGCCCUGUGUCAGGGACCCCCAAGCAGCUAGCCAGCAUCAAAAUAAUCUACCCCAAUGACUUGGCAAAGAAGAUGACCAAAUGCAGCAAGAGUCACCUGCCGAGUCAGGGCCCUGUCAUCAUUGACUGCAGGCCCUUCAUGGAGUACAACAAGAGUCACAUCCAAGGAGCUGUCCACAUUAACUGUGCCGAUAAGAUCAGCCGGCGGAGACUGCAGCAGGGCAAGAUCACUGUCCUAGACUUGAUUUCCUGUAGGGAAGGCAAGGACUCUUUCAAGAGGAUCUUUUCCAAAGAAAUUAUAGUUUAUGAUGAGAAUACCAAUGAACCAAGCCGAGUGAUGCCCUCCCAGCCACUUCACAUAGUCCUCGAGUCCCUGAAGAGAGAAGGCAAAGAACCUCUGGUGUUGAAAGGUGUUCAUGAUAAAAAGCAAGUCUUUUGUGUCUUCAUGAUCUGAAGAGAGGAAACAACACGGAUCAAGAUGAUCCUAGACCUCCUAAUCAUGGGGAUGAUUACAAGGAGUUGCAGACCCUACUCUCUAUUUUGCAGUGGGUGGAGUUGUGGAUAGGGGUGACCCAUCAGUCAUUGAGAAAUGAAUCUCCUGGGUGCUACUUGUGAAAGUGAGGAUCCUCUCUCCCUUUCCUGUGGAUGCAGCUGAGAUUCUGGACAGCCUAGACUUCUUCCUCAGUGUCAGAGUAAGAUUGCCUCAAUGGGGCGGGGCAGGACACACUGCUGACCUCACCACUGGGCGCCCUGGGCAGCCACUGCGAGGCCUCGUCAUUUUCGAGUUGGUGAGACACCGCGGCAGUCGACUUGGAAGAUGCUCUGGUGGUAGAGGUUAGAUUAUUUGUAGUUUUGGGGGCCUUUUCUUCAAAUAUCUGGGAAUUUCAUUGAAAAUAUGUAGUUCAGGAGUGAAGGGGUCUAUAUUCUACUUUAUAAUUAUCAUUAUCAUUUUGGUAUCUUUUGGGAGAAUGGCCUAAAAUUGGGACCAAGAUGGAAAAGAAGGGAAAGGAAUGGGUCAAUAUUAGAAUGCCCUUCGUUAUCCUUUCAACUUGGUAAACCAGAGAUUAAUACCAUAGCACCACUGUGGUGAAAGACGGGGUGGGCAUUCCCCAAAGGCAUGACCAGCAGACUUCUCUCAGAUUCUUGAGUGGGUCAAGCAGACCAUUCUGGUCUGGCUUCUCCUCUCAGAUUUAUUUGAGUAAUCCCCUCCCUUGGUGAUAAGAUUGUGUUUCAGCAAGAGUGGUAGUGGUACCAUUUCGGAAGGAGUAAUUUUUGCAGGGAAGUUGGUGGGAGGGGGGCAUAGUUAGAACAUAAGGAGGAAACUUCUAAAGGCUUGUUAGUUUAUUUUCAGAGAUUUCAGUACAAUCUUGGGUAAUUUAUGGCUGGCCCAUCUGAUGCUCUGGUUUAUGUUUGUAAACACUGGUUGCUACCCUCCCUGUCCAAGAUCCUUGUCCCCCUGUCUCCAUGCCAUACUCUCCAUUUUUGGUGCUGUCUGUCAAGUAGAGCGGCUGCUAACUUGCCAUUUUAGUAAUGCUGUGUCAGGUUGGGAAGAAACCGAUCAGAGGCAUGGCAGCCCCUGGGAUUAAGUUACUGUUCUAAUUUACAGUGCCCUCCCUGUUGUGACCUAUGCUAGAAUCUAUGUUUUAGUCUCAUCUUCUAAAGAAUAAAUGGCAUCAGACCUGUGCUUCUCUUCAACCUGGUGAAAAUGAUCCAAAUGAAUAAAUAUUUAGGGAUUUGUGAGGUCUUUGAAAGAAUUAUAUUGUUUUACUCAAAGCUGAUUUUUAAUCAACUAAAACUUGCUUUCUAGUCAAACUGAGUAAGAAAGUUGAACAAUUCUAGACCAUCCAUAACGAGAGCUACCGUUUUUGCUAUAAAGUUUUUCAGGCUCCCUUUCUUUUCAGUAAAGCUGGGUCCAGGGAAAUAAUUUGUCAUUUACUUAGGUAGGAAGAAAUAGUCUACUGCCCCUUUUUCUUAAAGACAGUAUAUGCCUUCAAAAAUGUUAUUAUAAACAUUUUCAAGCAUAUAGAAAAGCAGAAAAGUGUGUAAUGAACAUCCAUACACCUAUCAACCAGAUUAAACAAUUAUAUUUUUCCUAUUUGCUUUCUCUUUUCUGUUGAAAUAUUUAAAAAUAUAGAUAAUGUUUUAAUGUAUUUAAGUAUGUUUAAUGUGUAAAUUAAUGUUUCAAAUUCAAUAAAGCUGGAAAUAUUUUAUAGUAUACUAUGAACAUUUUCACUCGUAAACA